ACAGAGACAUGUACACGCGCGCGCACAGCCGCUCUCCCUCAGACACACUGGAGGGAAAGGUCAAACUAAAGGCGAGGGAGCAGAGAGACCGGAGGGAGCCGCUGCCGCCGCCGCGCGCCAUGACGGACGCGGCGGAGGCUGCUUUCUCAGUGCGGACGCCGCCGAUCCCCAGCUCUCGCCGCGCCCCCUGCCCCCCGCCCCUCGCGCGCCCCUCACCCUGGCGCUGGCGCGUCCCCGCGCCCUCUCCCCCGGCCGCUCCAGGCGCGCCUCGGGCUCGGGGCGCGGGGCGCUGGGAGCGGGAGGGUGGGGGCCGCGGCGGGCCGGCGGCCUCCUCGCCCGACCCCCGACCCCGGGCCAGGUGUCUUCAGAAUUCGGCAAAGUAGAUGGGACUGCAGACGUUACCAUUCCCUGUGACUCUUGCUACGAUCUUACAGACUUCAUUGUGCUGGGCUUAGAUGUCUUCAGAGUCACCAGGUACUUGGUUGUUCCUAGAUAGUGGGCCUGCCUGAUCAGGAUUUGGUAUUUUUCCCACUGAAUUAAAAUUGUUUUGCCUAAGCCUCAUUUUGUGUGUCAAGAAAAUAAAGGCAAAAGAGUAAGUGCUGUGCUCCUAAUCCACAGCUAGCUGGUAGUCAGCAGCCUGGGAGGCUGAGUCUCUGGUCUCCUAGUCUCAACCUUCUAGGCAGUGAGCAUUGUUAAUCACAGAACAGGCCCUCCUUGGACUCCUUGGCUUGCUCGUCUUUGUUUCUCCCAGGGCCUAGCGUUCACAUCCACACACAUACUACAUACGUUUCUGCAUGUGUGCAUGUGCAUGUCAGGGAAACCACAAUUUGUUCUCAGCUCCUUACUCAUGUGAGCUUAGCGAAAUCGUUUCUCCAAUCUGUACCUUCUUCUUCAUCUGUAAAAUAGAAUUAUCAUCUGCUCUGCUACUACCCUUAAAAGUAGUUACUGCAUAAGGAUGAGAAAAUGUAUAAAAACACUUUGAAGCUUUUGUUACAAAGGGCAGUUAGUAAUAAUGAGUAAAUGAUAAAUAAGCCUUAUAGAACAGGAAGCCUUUUCAUCUUUCUGUCCUAAACACCCUUCUAUUUUAUAAAUUUUUCAAGUAGAUUAAGUUUAUUAAUUUAGAUAAUGUUUUCUUUUUCUUUUUGUCUCUGCUCUAUUUAUUUAACAUUGGAUAUAUAGAGAAUGGUAAUUAUUAUUGAAUGGAUUGAAAACAAGAAUAGAGUCUCUUUGGGAGUAUCUGUGUUUUUUGUUUUUUUUUUUUUCCAUGUAAUUGGGGGCAUUUUCUGCUCCAUGGUCGGUUUCUGGUGGUUUGUGAAUUCUUGCCUUCUGCCAAGUGUUUUCUCCCUGUCACCACCCUGCUACUACUCUUUGUGUUUACCUUCCCAGCUGCCCUGCCUUAUUUCAGAGUUCAGAGUCAAAUUGUAGCCAACCAUUUCUGACAGCCUUCCUAGACAUCACUGAAUUUCAGCUAAUUAAUAGAUUUAAGGGAUGCGAAAUCUAGGCCAAUUCAGAAUUUUACUUCAUUUGAGGGUUUUUUUUCCAGAAUAUUUAUCUUAAGUUACAAAAUGUUGUUUCCUGUUAAUUGUUUUCUUAUGUAUUCUGGUAAAAUUUUAUAAACCCAGUAAAACUCUCUUACAACAAUACUCUUGGGAGAUAAUGGCUUGUAUUCGUUCUGGAUUGUCACAUAGGAAGAGAUGUGUUUAGGUAUCUAACUUGGUUUCAGCAUUGUACUUGAGACAUCUGUGGUAGGACAGAAUCUGUGGCAAAUGUGGCAUGGCAUACAUUAUAUAUGGAUAUUCAUAAACUGCUUUUGAUAGAUUGACAAACAUUUCCAGUUACUGAACCAGUAGCACUGUUCCAGUCAGUAGCUCAGUAAUAUCCAUUUUUUUGUCUGUACAGCAGAUUGUAUGUAUGCAUGUGUGUUUUGCCCAUUUUUAUAAAAAUGUGUUAAAAGUAAAAUGCUAAUGCUGAUAGAAAAUUGACCCGCAAAUAUGUAAUGUUUUUGACAAAGAUGGAAAUCAUAAAGCAUGCCAAAAAUGGUAAACCUUUAGCUUCAGCUAUCCCCUCAUUAGACUUUACCUUCUUACUGUGUAUUAUUACAAAGAUUGUGUCUAGAAGAUACUUUAUAAUGAUAGAAGGUAUUUUAUAAUAGGGUUUCUUAUCACAUAUACUUAAUAUUCAACUUCUGUACAUUUAAUUUUCAUGUUUCCUCAAGAAUAUAUUAUACAAAGUCAUAGCAUUUGACAAAAUUCCUUCAUAACUCUGAAGAAAAUAUUCUAUGUAUUGUUUGUGUGAGUUAAAUACAGUGGCUCUGAUAAAAAUGUCUUUUGAUCAGUCUUUAAAAAAAUUAAACUGAGGACAGGAAGGUAAAUUAAAGGGGAGAUUUGGAGACUUGUGGUAACUGGUUUAUUGCAACUUAAUGUGCAGCAUCCUCAUUAGUCAAGUAUCAUGUGCCUACCUAGGCAUGAAAUAGCUAUUUUUUUCCUGAUUUAAAUCUGGAAAGUUUCAGUUGUAGUACAGUUUGAAUAGUUGUUGUUGUAAAUAGCCACUGGACUUUUUAAAAAAGUAUUUUUCUUCAAAAACAGUGAAGGUCAUCUUGUAUCCAUAGAGACCACAUGUACUUUCCUCAUUAUUUCCAGCAUUAUUUAUAUAAUGGGUAGAGUUAUUUACAACAUUAAACAAAAAGUAUUUCAGAGAGCAACCGUUAAAUAUUAUCACAGGGUAAAUAUCAGCAACUGAAAUCCUUUUCUCAUAGUUUCUCAAAAAAUUUGGUAUUAGGAAAUUAAUAGUCUCUCAGAAUUUGUAUAUUGGUUUUCUUCAGUAGUUAUUCUGUAGAGUGUGUGUGUACAUAUGCAUGCUCAUGUAUGUAUGUAUGUUCAUUUCUUAAAUCAUUUCAUAAAUCACUGUGACUUAAUUGUGGACUUUAAUUGUUUUCAUAGUUUUUUUCCCCAAAAGAAGGUUACUUUACAUAUUUUAUUUUAUUUUUAUUUUUAUUUUUUUUGAGACAGGGUCUCACUCUGUCGCCCAGGCUGCAGUGCAGUGGCAUGAGCUCAGCUCACUGCAGCCUCCACCUCCCAAGCUCAGGGAUCCUCUUACCUCAGCCUCCCGAAUAGCUGGGACCGCAUGCACCACCACACCCAGCUAAUAUGUUGUAUGUUUUUAGAGGUAGGGUUUUGCCACUUAGCCCAAGGCUGGUCUUGAACUCCGGGACUCAAGCGAUCUACCCAUCCACCUGCCUCGGCCUCCCAAAGUGCUGUGAUUAUAGACAUGAGCCACUGUGCCUGGCAAUUUUACAUAUUUUAAAUUAAAGCAAAUCUUGGUUUUUGAUGGAAUGCAGAUUUACUUAUAUUUCACUUAGUCUUUUUCCUUUCUUUCAGAAAAGUGGUGUGGAAACAAAAUGGUUUUAGUAUAUUGCCUUAUAAACAAAUUUAAGAUCAUGAGUUUCUUUUAUUAUCCUCUUUGUUUUGCUCAUUUCCUUGAACUGUACAUCCCUAACCUAAAUCAGCUGGAGACAGGGGAAGAAAGUGUUAGAUUCUUACUCAGUUUAGAUCCUCUGCCAGGAAAACCCACUCUAUUCAUUGUCAACUAAAUUAACGCUUUUUUAAAUAAAAGGAGUCAUUUUUAACAAUAACGUCAGGGCAGCAGGCAUCCAUGAAAUGUAUGGUCACUGAUCAUUAGGGUUAUCAUUCUAAUGUGUUUACUAUUUUGAAACUCUAGGGAGAAGAAAACUUAUUUUUGCAUAUGUUGGAAAAAUGUAUCCUCAUGUAGGAUAUCAGGGUAAUAUCUUUAAUGUUUCAUACUUACCAAGAUAAAUUUGUAAUGCGUAUUUUCUUUUAAAAUUAGAUUUAUUUAGGAGAAAUUGCACUUGGUGAACCACUUUCUCUUUAAUUAUUAGCAUUAACUUUAUCAUUUUUGUUUCAAGAUGUCACAGCUAUUGUUCAGCACUAGAAAUUAUAUAAAUUAUUAGCUGAAGAUGAUGACUGGCAACAUUUAUGUCUGUUCCUCCUCUUAAAUUUCUUGUUCAGAAAGUCUGUUGUUGUAAACAUCCCCGACUGGAAGCUGUAAGACACAGCUAAGCUUUCAGUCAGAUGUUUGCUGCUACCGGCUAUUCACAGACAUCCUCUUGAUAUAAUUCUGUCCCGGAGUGGAGUUGAGGAGGCUAUAAAAUGUGUGGGAAAACCUCAGAAAUCUUUAGCUGCAUUCUUUUACUGCACUGACAGUGCACGUAUUAUGAUAGUUGAAUGUAGGGUGCUCUCCUAAUAACAGGAUAUGCCGUCUCGAGCUUCCCAGACUUAGCGUGCUGCUGCUGGGCCUUAGAGAAUUUAGUUAAAUAAAAAGUGUCACCGCCUAUUCCUGUUUCUGCCCUGUCAAUGAAAUUUUAGUCUUUAUAACCUUUCCAAGUAGGCUGGAGUUUAACAUCCCAACAAUUCAGGAGACUGAUUUUCUCCAUUGUAAAUUCUGUGGAAGUUCUGGAGAAUAAUUUCAUCACUACCACCCAGCAGUAUGCAAUCUAGAAAUUUCAGCUUUCCCUAUACUUAAAAGAGAUGUGUGUGCAACAUUUUUCUCCGUCCUCUUAGCCCCCCACUUCCUGUUCCCCUCACCCUGAGUGAUAUUACAGCUCCUAAUCAGAACUCUCCUCUAAGAAAAACUGCAAGACGUCAAGCCACUAAGCCUGUUUACAUUUGCUAAUGGGUAUGCAUGUCUUUUUAUAUUAAUAUUUUUCCUAAGUAUUUUCAGAUUGUUGCUUUCAGAUUUAUUGCUUCCUCCUUAAAAUAUAGCUGCCCUGAAAGCAGCUGUAUUGUAUCUAUUUUUUGUGUUUCCCCACAGAUCUGAAUAAUCCAGGGCUUUUCUCACAGAUGACACUCAGUGUGGACUAAUUGAUAAUGUAUAAUUUUAUAGCAACUAUUUUCUGAGUUUUAAAAAAUUGUUAUUUUAUUUCUGUUAGUCUUUCAGACACUGGAAAACAUUUCUAUUUUAUUGGCAUUUUUCUUUUCAAUAAAGCAUUGGUUUUUUUAAAUCAUUUAUUUUUAUUAAACUGCUAAACAUACUAUGUUAGGUUCCAUACAUGAUUAAACCACCAAAAGAUAAAGGUCUUGCCAAUCUAAUGUAUUUACAUGCUUAUUUUCUUUGAUUAGAUUAUAAGCUUUCUGAGGUCAGAGACAUUAAAUCUUGAUAAUUCUAUUUUUUCCUGUUAUAAACAGCAAGUAAAGCACCUUGCAUGUAUAGUACUUUAGUAAUGAUUUUAUAUUAUCUUAUUGCAGCAGUGUCUACUGUUGCCUCUUAUCUUUUAUCCAGAUGAGCAAAUGACAGUUUUGGUCAUAAUGUAGUUACCCCAGAUGUAUUUGUGCUACAGCUUUUAUUUUUUAAAUGCUCUUUUGUUAGAGUAGUAGUUUAUAAGACUUAUUUGGGGAUGGGGGUCAGUUGCUUCAGACUCAGGUGGCUUUCCAACUUGUAAAUACAAUUUUCAGGCUGGAUGAUUAGCAUGCAUCAAGCAUCCCUUCCUAUGAACUCUAAAUAAAGCAGAUUUAUUGCAUAUUCUGUGGCCCUCUGUUUUAGCACAUUGGAAACCUUAGACUCAAAUAGCAGUGAAAGGAUAGUUAUUGCUGAGCUCAGAAGUCUUCCCUGCCAAAGGUAGAAUGUAAUGUGUUCUGUGGUAAUAGGAUUAUUUUGUUUGACCAGGUGACACUGUUUAUUUCUUAUGAAAAAUUUUGAUAUACUGCUUUAAAAUUUAGUAAGAUGGAUGCAUAAUUUAUGCAGUGAAAUUUGAAAGGUUUUUCAAAAUGAUAAGGCCAAACCUAAGCUAAAUGAGGGGGUAGGCAUUCUUUAUAAUAAAGCUGUUAUACUCUGCCCAGCUAGGCCAGUUAUCCCUAGAUGCUACAGAUUAAUGGGGCAAUCUGUGUUAUGUAACAUUUGUUCUAUAUUAUUCUGCCUCUAAUGAGGUGAAUCAAAGACGAUGUCAGUUUUAAUUCUGGAUGCCCUUGCUUCAGUAUAGUAUAAUACAUAGGUACAGCCUUUUUUAGUAGUUUUCAGAUGGCUUCUUUAUGUUUUUAUAUUGAAGAACCACUAACUUCCCAUUGGCCUAUAAGGUUAGCAAUUGAUUAUUUAUAGCAAAUGGCUUGAAAUGUUAGAUCAUCAGUAUUUGUCAAUAAGCCUGUAAUAACUUGUUUCCCUAGCCCUUAACUUAGUGUUGAAGAAAAAAAUUGUGGUAUUCAUUGAUAGGACUUAGAAAGCACAGAAAUUACUUAUUAUUUAAGAUUUGUUCUACCAAUUGAUAUUUAAAGUAAAACAUUUUUAGUUACUGAACACCAUUCUGUAAAUGACAGUAUUUUAUCCUGAGUAUAUGGUCUGAAAUGACUUAGGGACAACUUUUUAAAGCAAAUAACUAAUUACAAAAUUGGGUCUUCCAAUUUAUUUCAAAUUAGAUGCUUUUGUACAAAUAUUCUUGGUUAGAAAUAGUCAUAUAAAUACACUGUUGGACUUGUUCUCAUUGAUCUCCACACCUCAGUUCCUUCUACAUGAGUCAUGGGCUUGAGGUUACCCAGAAAUGGACUGUGAACCUAUAAACCCCAGCAUGCAUGUGGUAUUGCGUCGAGCAUGUUCUGUGAUUCCCUUCUACUCUUGUUACAGCUUUAUUCAUUGGAUCAAUGUGCAUUAUUUGCUGUGUGUGCUCAGGUAAUAUUUUUGUUUCUUUUUUUUAGUUUGAAUAUCAGUUUGGGCUUAGUUACUUUUUAAAAUAAGGCUGUUUCAGAUAGUCUCUGCCACACUUUGCCUAGCCUGGUUAAUUGUGGGUGGACCCAUGCUACAUGUUUUGGCAUUGCCUUUUUCUUAUCUGUACCAUAUUACAAACUUCCUAGUAAUUUGACAUUCACUGCUGUCUUUGCUUUAGCUUUCCAACAGGUUUGGUGAAACAGUCCAUUGCUGUUCAAUAUCAGCUUGCAUCAGAAUUACUUGGAGGGCUUAUUGAUUAAAACACAGAUUGCUGGGCCCUGCAAAAAAAGUUUCUGAUUCAGUAGGUCUGGGGUGGAACAUAAGAAUGUGCUUUUCCCCCCACAGUUCCCAAGUACUGCUGAUGCUGCUCCUCUAGGCCCAUGCUUUCAGAAUCACAGAGCUCAUCUUACAUUCUUUUCCUGCUAGAUAUUAUGCCCAAUUAAUACAUGAAGUAAAACAGAAAAAUCCUUAACUUAAAAACAUGUAUUAAUCCAGAAGUUUGAUUAUAAAAAGGUUUGUUGAAAAUGUGAGACCAUUUUUUCUCCCAGAGAAAAAGUAUAUUAAUUGUCUAGCUGGGAGGGGCCUAUUUGAAUGUGUUUUCAGAGAAAAGCAGAAGAAAAAAAUACGGUUGUAAUAGAAGUAGUUAAAACAGAAAAGCAGUAUGGUUGUAGAGUGGGGUGGCGGGGAGGUAUAUGUGUAUUUAAUCUUGAGAACCAAUGCUUUUGGAAAACAGCCCGAAGGGACAAGAGACUAGGUAGAGACUGGCGAGGUUCCUGAAAGUCCUGGGUUACCUGUGAAAUGCCAAAGAUUUUUAAAGUUUGCUGGCAGUGGUUAUUAUAUGUAGUUUUACUUCCAAAUUUGAAGAUUUCCUCUUCUUUGAUGCAAGUGUGUUGGUAGGACCACUGAUAAUAGUUAGUGGAGAUAUUUGUGGGAAUAUAUUUUUAAUCAGAAAGAAUGCAAAAAGAGGGGGAGACAUUUCUUUGAGACACCUUAAUGACACUGGGAACAGUAGAAGGUGGAAAGAGAUCAGAGUGUGGGAAAGAUGUGCCUGAGAUGAAAUUAUCUGAAUUCUGAAUGUGGGGGAGAAGAUGAGGAGAGGGUUGAGGGGGAGGAGAGAUGACUAAGCUCCUCACAGUGUUUCAUUAACUGUCUUUUACCUAAAGGAGGAAUCUUCUUAAUGAAGAUUGGUUGAUGCAUCAUACUGGUCAUCAAGUAAGUUCUUAUAAAUGCAAGUUUGAUUGUUUUGAAGGGAAGGAUAUAGGAAGGCUGGAUAAUCAGCUACAUUUAGAUAUGGAACACUACAGGAUGUCGGCAUUUAUUGUUGUAAAUUCCUUUGGUGAAAAACGUUAUCACUUGUUUGUGACUAGCCUGGGCAAUAUAGUGAGACCUUGUCUCUAAAAAAAAUUUUAUUAAUAAGAAAAAUUAGCCGGGCAUAGUAGCGUGCCUGUAGUGCCCCCCACUGCCCUGGACACGCCCCCACUUCCAAAAAAACAAACACCCAACUCACUUCUGCCUUUUCCUUGGAUUCUACACUUUCUCUCAGGAUAUCUUUCCGAUUGAGUCUUGCCUCAUUUAUGUGAAUGCUGUGCCUGUUCUUUUUUUCAACAGAGUCUUACGUAAAGAACCGUACAAACUUAGUAAAGAGUUUAAGUCCUGCUUUAAACCAAGUUUCAGUUCAUGUAAACAUCCUACACUCAGCUGUAAUACAUGGAUUGGCUGGGAGGUGGAUGUUUACUUCAGCUGACUUGGAAUGUCAACCAAUUAACAUUGAUAAAAGAUUUGGCAAGAAUAGUAUACAGAGGCUUGAAUUUUUAAUGUAAUUAAUGUAAUUAAAGGUUUGUUGGAAAUGUGAGACCAUUUUGUUCUCCCAGAGAAAAAGUGUGUUAAUUGUCUAGCUGGCAGGGAUCUACUUGAAUAUGUUUGCAGAGAAAAGCAGAAGAAAGCAUGGUUGCAGUAGGAGUAGUUAAAACAGAAAAACAGUAUGCUUAUAGAGGAAAAAUUACUCUAAAUUUAUUAAAAUUCCUUUAAAUUUGUUACUCAAUUUAAAUUUUUAUUGUAUCUUUUCAAUUUUGCUAUAGCACUAACAUGACAUAAGGCUCUGGGUAUUGGGACAAAAGAAUGCCCUUGUUUGGUAGUUGGGGUCGGGUUUGUAGUAUUGCAGUGUGCUUUAACAAGCAUGGGCUUUGACAUCAGACAUUUGUUGCCAUCUGGACUCCACAAGUGAAUUUGCUACGGGAUUUGGAGGAGGGAAAGGCACUGUUUCCAUACCUCAGUGGUUUUCUCAUCUGUAAAAUAAGUAUGUGAUUGCAUGGAUUGACUUACAUGAUGAAUAUAAAGUUGUUCAUUAGUACAGUACCUGUCAUAUUAAGUACUCAAUAAAUGCUAGUUAUUAUUAAUGCUGUGUUGUAGGUGUUCAGUAAAUAGUUGCCAUAAUGCUUAAAGCAGACAUAACUUGUUUUUAUUUUUGCAAUAAAGAUGAUGCCAACUUUUUGGUUUAAUGGAAAUGCUUUGAAUCUUUGAUAUUGUUGUAAUAUAGUGGCAAAGAAUUUUGAAUCCCAGCUUCUGGAGCUCAUAUCUUGAUUCUGCGAGUUACUUCGCUAUGUUACUUUGGGGGAAGUUAUUAAUCUCUCUGUGCCUCAGUUUCCUCAGUCGACUAAAUUGAAAUUAUAAUAGCACCUACCUGAUAGGAUUGUUGAGACUAAAUGAGGUAACAAUUUAAAAAUAAGCUAAUACCUGAUAAUUAGUUCUAUAUAUGUACUGAUUGGUCUAAACGUUAUUUCCAUUUUCAUGUCUUUACUUAAAAUACUGAAAAUUAAUUUUUUAUAGCUUUGUUUUUCAGUUCCAUGAAAUCAGCCUGCCUUUUCUUUUUUUGGUGAUACAUCCACAUUCUGUAUAGGUGAAAAGCAAAACAAACAAGUAUAAAACGAAAAUUAUGUAAGAAGUACACACAUCCUAGCAGCUUGGCAAGUGUCUGUAUGCUCUUGCCUGUGCCUAAAUCCAGAAUUAGAAUUCAUGCUUGGUGCUCCUGUGGAAGAUGUCUAAAUGUUAUGAGAAAUACAUGAUUAAAUAAAAAUGUGAAAUGAAAGCAUGGAGACUUGUUGAAGGUUGUAAGUGAAGAUACAGAUGGCAAGACACACAAAGACCAAAUCCCAAAGCACUUCAACAUUUAGAAGUCAGAAAAAGAAAGAGAAACUAGCAAACAAUACUGAGAAGAGGCCAAUGAAAUCAGGAAAAUCAGGAGAUGAUGGUGUCUGAAAGCCAAACAAGGAAAGGCUACCAAAAAGGAUGAAGAGAUCAACAGUGUCAAAUUCUCCUGAAAGGACUGCCCUUAUUGGACCACAGAGAGAAAGAUGAUCUCCUUCCCAGGUGCACUGAGUGGCAGCCUUGGGCCUGGACUGGUGGGUUCUUGGUGGCAGCAGGCAUUUGCUGGUGGGGGCUCCCUCAGACCAUUUUCAACUAUUAAGUCAAGAGGACUUACAGCAAGUUCUUGCAAUCUUCACUCCCAUGUGCAUGAAGUCUUGGGUCCAUGAUGUUCUGCCACAGUUUACAAUGACCUUCAUUAUGCAUCAUUAGCAUUUCAUUAACAUUAGCAGGGCCAUAUAGCAGUUUAAUCUAUCAGCUACUCCCUUAGGACAUCUGGCUAAUCCAUUAACUUCCAACAUAAAUUAUUGAACCCCCCUUUUAGCUGGUUAUUUAUGAGACCACUGGUCCUGACCUGCCCUUCCUGGUUUUGGCAUGGUUCCUAGUCUUCUGGAAGUCUUUGACUUACUCUUAGUAAACUUAUCUGCCCCUCGAAACUUACACAAAUAUACCAUUUCAUAAACAGACAUACAGAACUUCAAGUAAGAAAUAGGACCCCAUAUCUACCAAACCUGUCUCUUUACUAAAAUAUCCUAUUUUGACCCUUUCUUUGAAUUGUAACUAGUUUUGUAAUUACACAGUUAUAUGUCUAUUUUUGCAUAUACAAUGUUAACUUUUUAUCAGUAAAGCCUCAUGGCUCAACUUGUAGAUCAACAACCAUAGAUCUACAGUUGUUGUGAUAUGCAAAUUGUCACUGCCUCUUCCUUUGUCCUUUCAGCACUAACCCAGCAUUUUUGGAAGGAACCUGGUUUUCUGAGAAUAGCAAUAUGUUUCAGGCCAUUCUGAUGUUCCCUUACUCCCACACAUGGAAUUAGCUUCUUUGAAGGGGCCCUGGCUACUGCUAAUGAAAACCACUCCGGAGAUUAAUACUUGGGUACUGAGAGUACACACAGGUGUGCACAGGCAGACCGGGGAUGUGAUGGCACUCCAUGGCCACUGGAAAGACAGGUGGAAAAGAUGCUGUUUCCUAAUCUUGUAAUUAUGUUCAUAGUGAGAUUGCUCAUAUAGUUCUAGCAUUACUACAUCCUUCUCUUUUAUAUGAUUUUUAAGUGGAUUAUUUUCUACAAUGUGCCUAUUUAGAUUUUUAACUGUUAACCCAAACUGAUUAUUCCCACCUCUGAUUUUAUCAUUUUAUAGAUAUAUAUGUGUGUGUGCAUACAUAUGCAUAUAUAUAUAUAUGUGUGUGUGUGUGCAUAUAUACAUAUAUAUAUAUAUAUAAAUAAAUUUUAGGGACAGGGUCUUGCUUUGUUGCUGCCCAGGUUGGAGGAGUGCAGUGGCAUGAUCACAGCUUAUUGCAGCCUUGAGCUCCUGGGCUCAAGCAAUCCUCCAGCCUUGGCCUCCCAUAGUGUUAGGAUUACAGGCAUGAGCCACCAUGCCCAGCCAAGAUCCAUUAUUUUGAGGUCGCCUGUAUGUAUCCUUUAUCAAAACCUUCUUUCAAGAAAGCAUCCUGUGAAAUUAUGUUCCUAAAUUAUUGUUUUCAUGUAAAUGUCUAUUUCUCAUAAAGAUAUUGGAUAUAAUGAUAAAAUUAUUGACACGAAUAUAUUCAGUUGUGCAAAUUAUAUUUCUUAUAUAACUAAAUACCAUUUCAUGUCGAUAAAUUUAUUGACACAAAUUAAUUCACAUACUAGCUUCAAGAGGCCAACUGCCACCAGUGGUCAGCUGGGAAGCCGCUCUCUUCUAGGAACCAUCACCGAGGCAGCUUGCCAUUAAUUAUAUACUUUCGAGUGAUUUACAUCCAAUUCCACAAAUGUGUCUUCAUUAAUUGAAGGCAUUCUGAAAUAUUACUGGCAAAUAGAAAGAAUAGAGAUGUUUGCUGAUUGAAAAUGUGCAAAUCACAUAGUAAGGCCGUGGAAGAGCCAGCUGUGGACUCAUCUCUCCAUUUACGAACCUGGAUUCCCCCACAGAAAGGGGCCAUCUCUUAGUCAUUUCCAUCUGCCUAUGGCCAGGACAGUUUCCAGUAAUAAUAGGUGCUCAGUAACUCUUCUCUGAAUGAUGAAUGGGUAGGAGGAAGAAAAUGCCAUGGGAAUAGUGGAGAAAAUCAUAGCUUUCCAAAUAAUUAACCCAGAACCAUCAUCCACAGUCCACAAUUUCUUCUUUUAAUUUGUCUUCAGCAGUCUGAGGUAAUUGGGUUUUGAGACAAAUUUUAAAUUGUUUCAUUUCCAAAAUUCGUUUGGUCACAACAUCUAGGAGCAAUCCAUCUGCUAAUCAAUAAACAACAUUUAAACGCUGCUGUGAGAAAGGCAAACCGGCACAAAACCAAUACUGUCAGCAACCCAGAACAACUCUAAUUUCCUGACAGAAAUCGAUUCACAGCAAAAUAAUGAUUAUUGUAAAUAUUUAUAGUUCUAAAAGGAAACGCUCAUCAAUGCAGCUUUUUGAGCAGUUCAUUUCCAAAUAAAGAUUCUGAUGGGCCCCACCUAGCCAUGUAUCUUGUGGUGGAGGACGUGGUGGCUGUGAAGCGACUCUGUGGCUGUCUUGGAACUGGCUCUCUUGGAGGCUCUCCUGGAGGCCUGGGGGGCAGUUUGGGUACAUUUUAGAUGUGGUGGGGAGAGGAACACUGGGCAUGGAGAGGCGAGAUCCACACCUGGCUCUUCACUAUUUUGCUGUGUAAUCUCAGAAAGCCAUUUGACCACUCUGAACAUUCCAUUUUCUCAUCUGGAAAAGGACAAUAAUCAUAUUGCCCAACUUAACCUUCCAGAUUGCGAGGAUGAAAUGAAGAAGGGGGAGGCUAUAUCUGUGAGCAUAUAUUUAACAGACUGGACAACUUUAGGGUCUUUUCAUGGUUCCGUAUUUCCCAAGAACAGGGUUAAGGAGCAGGCGGGCAGUCUCCUGAGAAAUCAGAUGAGUCAUCCUGAAGCUCAAUGCCCAAGGGAGUUUUCCUCCUAAAAAAUAAGUGACCCCAGAACGAAGUGUUCAUUCAGUAAUAUGACUAUGCAACAGGCGCUGAGAAAACAAGAUGAAAAGGACCUAUAAGGGCUGCUCAGGAAGCUCAGUCUAGUGAGGAUGAACGCUGUGCAAACAGAGAAGUGGGGGAUGGAGCUAGGCCAGUGAGACCAGAGCUGUGGGAACAUGAAGUGUGAACUUCAGGGCUGUCCGAGAAUUUCAUGUUGAGCAGCAACCAAAGAGGGUUAUUCCAGGAAAAGAAGAACAGGCAAAGACUAGCAUUUCAGGGGAACCAUGAACACAAAUCAGUUUCCCAAACUUCAGUCUCCUGAAGUCUGCUUUUACACUUUUUUUUUUUGGGGGGGGGGGGGCAUGUCUUUGCAGCAUGUACACCAUUUUAAGUUGACUGAUUUUUGAAAAUGUAAACGAACAAUUUAAAAACUUUAUAUGACUACUGUAAGUGAAAAACGUUAUUUGUCAUGAACAGAAAAUGACCUUAGAACAUGGACCACAUCAACUCAUUACUCAUGAAAUAAAUAACUGUCAGGCUCAGUUUGUUUCUGAGGCUAACGGGGUGACCAUUGACAGAGGUAAGGGAGGGAGAUAAUGACAGAUAGGAAUGGAUGCUACGUAGAAAAUAUGAAGUGUCUUGGAGGGUUACUUUAGAUGGGUUUCGGGGGGUGAGGGUUAGGGGCUGGAAGAUAUCAUUUGAGCCGAGGACUACAGUGUUGGAGCUAAACACCUUAACAUCAAAACCAAAAACAAAGUCAUUAAAUUUCCACCAGACUCAGCUGCCUGCCGAAGGCUGUGCCACAAGCAGAGAAAUGAAUGAGCGGGUGUUGGAGGCGCGCACAUCCAGUGCAGACUUGUUGUGGGACAAAAAGAGACGAGAGAGGAGGAAGUCGCCUUGUCACGUGUGAUCGUAGGCCGCUCAGUGCUCUGUAGCCCCUAAAACCCAGCCGGGUGGCCCAAAGGAAAGCACCCCACGCUUCGGGAAACGCCGCAGCUUUGAGCGGGAUGCAGGUUGGGAGCACCCCGAUGGACACAUCAGUAAACUGAGAGCAAGAAAAGUUAAUUCGCUGCCCCAAGUUAGGUAGUGAGAGGUAGAGCUGGGACACGAAGCGCACCCAGAACUCUCCUUGCACGCCCAGCUCGGCGGCCCCACAUGCCGCGGGUCUAGGGUCGCGCUAGCAGAGGCCUGGCACAACCGCCAGACUCCUGACCCCGAGAUCCGCGCUCCGGACCUCCCGAGGGCCCCUCCCUGGGCGUGGCUCAAAACGCGGCGCAGCGGAAUCCGUGAAGUGGGAUAAAAAGCACGGCCUCCGACUGCGAGCAUGCGCGUUAGCUCGGCCCUGCCGGGCCGCGCUCGGCGCCGGGGGAGGGUCACCCGAAGCGGACGUCCGCUACGCAGGCGUCUGCGCCCCGUGGGGAGGAGGGCGAAGACUCCAUCCGCCAUGUUGGAUGCCGCAGAUUCGCCAUAACCUCGCCGGCUCUUUUCUUAAAAAAAUAAAAAUAAAAAGCGAAGCGUCAGCAGGGCGCCCCGCCCCCUCGGUCGGCACGGGAGGGGGCCCGGAAGAGCCCGAGGCUUUUUUUUCCUCCGCGGUGGGGCGUUGCCAUGGAGACGCGGGCGGCAGAAAACACGGCCAUCUUUAUGUGUAAAUGUUGUAACCUCUUCUCACCAAAUCAGUCGGAACUCCUCUCCCACGUUUCAGAGAAGCACAUGGAAGAAGGGGUUAAUGUUGAUGAGAUUAUUAUUCCCCUUAGGCCUCUGAGUACACCUGAACCCCCCAACUCAAGCAAAACCGGAGAUGAGUUUUUGGUCAUGAAGAGGAAGAGAGGCAGGCCUAAGGGGUCCACGAAGAAGUCCAGCACAGAAGAGGAGCUGGCAGAAAACAUCGUGAGUCCGACUGAGGACAGCCCGCUGGCUCCGGAGGAAGGGAACAGCCUGCCUCCAAGCAGCUUGGAGUGUAGCAAGUGCUGUCGGAAGUUCUCCAACACGCGCCAGCUGCGGAAGCACAUCUGCAUUAUCGUGCUGAAUUUGGGUGAGGAGGAAGGAGAAGCAGGUAACGAGUCUGACCUUGAACUAGAAAAGAAGUGUAAGGAAGAUGAUCGGGAAAAAGCCUCGAAAAGACCACGGUCACAGAAAACAGAGAAAGUCCAGAAGAUCUCAGGAAAGGAGGCCAGACAGCUUUCUGGGGCGAAGAAACCCAUCAUAAGUGUGGUUUUAACUGCACACGAAGCAAUUCCAGGUGCUACCAAGAUUGUGCCAGUGGAGGCUGGGCCCCCUGAAACAGGAGCUACAAAUUCUGAGACCACUUCAGCAGACCUGGUGCCUCGGAGAGGCUACCAGGAAUACGCCAUUCAGCAGACACCUUAUGAGCAACCAAUGAAGUCAAGCAGGCUAGGUCCCACUCAGCUCAAAAUCUUCACUUGUGAAUACUGCAACAAGGUCUUCAAGUUCAAGCACUCGCUGCAGGCCCACCUGAGGAUCCACACCAAUGAAAAGCCAUACAAGUGCCCCCAGUGCAGCUAUGCCAGUGCCAUCAAGGCCAACCUCAAUGUGCACCUGCGCAAGCACACUGGAGAGAAGUUCGCCUGCGACUAUUGCUCGUUCACCUGCCUGAGCAAGGGCCACCUCAAGGUGCACAUCGAGCGAGUGCACAAGAAGAUCAAGCAGCACUGCCGCUUCUGCAAGAAGAAGUACUCUGACGUCAAGAACCUCAUCAAGCACAUCCGAGACGCGCAUGACCCACAGGACAAGAAGGUCAAAGAGGCCUUGGACGAGCUCUGCCUGAUGACGAGGGAGGGCAAGCGGCAGCUGCUCUAUGACUGCCACAUCUGUGAGCGCAAGUUCAAGAACGAGCUGGACCGUGACCGCCAUAUGCUGGUCCACGGAGACAAGUGGCCUUUUGCCUGUGAGCUCUGUGGCCAUGGGGCCACCAAGUACCAGGCGCUGGAACUGCAUGUCAGGAAGCACCCCUUCGUGUACGUCUGUGCCGUCUGCCGCAAGAAGUUCGUCAGCUCCAUCAGGCUGCGCACCCACAUCAAAGAGGUGCACGGGGCUGCCCAGGAGGCCUUGGUCUUCACCAGUUCCAUCAACCAGAGCUUCUGCCUCCUGGAACCUGGUGGGGACAUCCAGCAAGAAGCUCUGGGGGACCAGCUACAGCUGGUGGAAGAGGAGUUUGCCCUCCAGGGCGUGAAUGCACUCAAGGAAGAGGCCUGUCCUGGGGACACUCAGCUGGAGGAGGGCCGGAAGGAGCCGGAGGCCCCUGGGGAAAUGCCUGCCCCAGCUGUGCACCUGGCCUCCCCGCAGGCCGAAAGCACAGCCCUGCCACCCUGUGAGCUGGAAACCACCGUGGUCUCCUCCUCAGACCUGCAUUCUCAAGAGGUGGUUUCAGAUGAUUUUUUGUUGAAAAAUGAUACCUCCUCCGCAGAGGCUCAUGCUGCUCCUGAGAAGCCCCCAGACAUGCAGCACAGAAGCUCAGUCCAGACGCAAGGUGAAGUGAUCACACUACUGCUGUCCAAGGCCCAGAGUGCUGGGUCAGAUCAGGAAAGCCAUGGCGCCCAGAGCCCCCUAGGGGAAGGGCAGAACAUGGCUGUGCUUUCAGCUGGUGACCCAGAUCCCAGCAGGUGUCUCAGGUCAAACCCAGCUGAGGCCUCAGACCUCCUCCCUCCAGUAGCUGGUGGUGGGGACACCAUCACACAUCAGCCUGACUCUUGCAAAGCUGCCCCUGAGCACCGGUCAGGCAUCACCGCUUUCAUGAAGGUCCUGAACAGUUUACAGAAGAAGCAAAUGAACACCAGCUUGUGUGAGCGGAUCCGGAAGGUUUAUGGAGACCUGGAGUGUGAAUACUGUGGCAAACUUUUUUGGUACCAAGUGCAUUUUGAUAUGCAUGUCCGCACCCACACCCGGGAACAUCUGUAUUAUUGCUCUCAGUGUCAUUAUUCUUCCAUCACCAAAAACUGCCUUAAACGCCACGUAAUUCAGAAACACAGUAACAUCUUGCUGAAGUGUCCCACCGAUGGCUGUGACUACUCAACUCCAGAUAAAUAUAAGCUACAGGCACAUCUUAAAGUUCACACAGCACUGGACAAAAGGAGUUAUUCUUGUCCUGUUUGUGAAAAGUCUUUUUCAGAGGAUCGAUUGAUAAAGUCACAUAUCAAGACCAACCAUCCUGAGGUCUCCAUGAGCACCAUUUCUGAGGUUCUCGGGAGGAGGGUUCAGCUGAAAGGGCUAAUUGGAAAGAGAGCCAUGAAAUGCCCAUAUUGUGACUUUUAUUUCAUGAAGAAUGGCUCAGACCUUCAGCGUCAUAUUUGGGCUCAUGAAGGUGUGAAGCCCUUCAAGUGUUCUUUGUGUGAGUAUGCAACUCGUAGCAAGAGUAACCUCAAGGCUCAUAUGAAUCGUCACAGCACUGAGAAAACCCACCUAUGUGACAUGUGUGGCAAGAAAUUCAAAUCAAAAGGGACACUGAAAAGUCACAAACUCCUUCACACUGCAGAUGGGAAGCAGUUUAAGUGCACGGUGUGUGACUACACAGCGGCCCAGAAGCCACAGCUGCUGCGGCACAUGGAACAGCAUGUCUCCUUCAAGCCUUUCCGCUGUGCCCAUUGCCAUUACUCCUGCAACAUAUCUGGCUCUCUGAAGCGGCACUACAACAGGAAGCACCCUAAUGAGGAGUAUGCCAACGUGGGCACCGGGGAGCUGGCAGCGGAGGUGCUCAUCCAGCAAGGUGGUUUGAAGUGUCCUGUUUGCAGCUUUGUAUAUGGCACCAAAUGGGAGUUCAAUAGGCACUUGAAGAACAAACAUGGCUUGAAGGUGGUGGAAAUUGAUGGAGACCCCAAGUGGGAGACAGCAACAGAAGCUCCUGAGGAGCCCUCCACCCAGUAUCUCCACAUCACAGAGGCCGAAGAAGACGUUCAAGGGACACAGGCAGCGGUGGCCGCGCUCCAGGACCUGAGAUACACCUCUGAGAGUGGCGACCGACUGGACCCCACGGCCGUGAACAUCCUGCAGCAGAUCAUUGAGCUGGGCGCCGAGACCCAUGACGCCACUGCCCUUGCCUCGGUGGUUGCCAUGGCACCAGGGACGGUGACUGUGGUUAAGCAGGUCACCGAGGAGGAGCCCAGCUCCAACCACACGGUCAUGAUCCAGGAGACGGUCCAGCAAGCGUCCGUGGAGCUUGCCGAGCAGCACCACCUGGUGGUGUCCUCCGACGACGUGGAGGGCAUUGAGACGGUGACUGUCUACACGCAGGGCGGGGAGGCCUCGGAGUUCAUCGUCUACGUGCAGGAGGCCAUGCAGCCUGUGGAGGAGCAGGCUGUGGAGCAGCCGGCCCAGGAACUCUAGAGGACAUGUGGCAUCGGAUGGCCACAGGGCGGGGCUGCCAGGCUCUGCAGGCACCCAGGGUGGGGAGGCCACCCUUCCUGCCCUACCCGCAGAAUGGUGCUCUCCUUUGCCCUCCCUGCCCAGCAGCCUGAUAGGACUCUCCUAGUCCAACUUGGGGUGGGCAAGGCAGUCAGCAUCACCAGCAAUACCACAGGACCCUCACCCCAGCAUAGACACACACCCCCUGACCCUUACCAUCUGCUUCCUGAAAGACUUCAGUGUCAGCUCCCCUACACACACCCCACACCUUCACCCCUUGCUUCAAGAUUCAAACAGAGACUCCCAGUCCCCCUCAGCAUCUUCCCUGAAUCACAGCCCCAGCUCCUUGACCCCCAUCUAGGUGCCAAAUGUUCAUCUGCAACCGCUAUGCAGUCUGGUGAGAGGGAGACAGCCAUCACAUAGAAAGUGACCGUACGGGUUUUUAAUCACUGCUGGGUGGGGUGGGGGUAGGGGGAUUGUCCUGGCUUUGUCGACAAAGUCCCACUUCCCCGAGUAUUAAGGGCCCUUGGUAUCAAGUGAGGUAAAUUCACCCAUCACAGGGUCUCGCCCUACCAUCCUGGAAUUAUUUCACUUUUAAGAUAAAUGCACUAUUUCACUGUUCGCCUCCCAUUCUAAGGAGGUGAGGUGGUUGGAAUAAAAACAGUUCCUGUCUGAA